AGAAGCUGGGCAGCCUCUGCCGGGUUCCGGGAAAAGGAGCUCCUGCUGCCACUGCUCUUCCGGAGCCUGCAGCAUGGGGCCCCUGCCGCGCACCGUGGAGCUCUUCUAUGACGUGCUGUCCCCCUACUCCUGGCUGGGCUUCGAGAUCCUGUGCCGGUAUCAGAAUAUCUGGAACAUCAACCUGCAGUUGCGGCCCAGCCUCAUAACAGGGAUCAUGAAAGACAGUGGAAACAAGCCUCCAGGUCUGCUUCCCCGCAAAGGACUAUACAUGGCAAAUGACUUAAAGCUCCUGAGACACCAUCUCCAGAUUCCCAUCCACUUCCCCAAGGAUUUCUUGUCUGUGAUGCUUGAAAAAGGAAGUUUGUCUGCCAUGCGUUUCCUCACCGCCGUGAACUUGGAGCAUCCAGAGAUGCUGGAGAAAGCGUCCCGGGAGCUGUGGAUGCGCGUCUGGUCAAGGGUGAGUGUGGGGCUCUGGGAAUCCUCUGGGAGGACCUUGGAUGACUUUCUGACCUUCCCCAGGCACGUUUUCAGGGUCAUGAUCCUGCCCCCGCCCGGGGGAUCUACUGUCCUCCCAGUCACACCCCUCUCCCCGCACCGCCUUCCUGCUGUCUUCUCUUCUUCCCAGAAUGAAGACAUCACCGAGCCGCAGAGCAUCCUGGCGGCUGCAGAGAAGGCUGGUAUGUCUGCAGAACAAGCCCAGGGACUUCUGGAAAAGAUCGCAACGCCAAAGGUGAAGAACCAGCUCAAGGAGACCACUGAGGCAGCCUGCAGAUACGGAGCCUUUGGGCUGCCCAUCACCGUGGCCCAUGUGGAUGGCCAAACCCACAUGUUAUUUGGCUCUGACCGGAUGGAGCUGCUGGCGCACCUGCUGGGAGAGAAGUGGAUGGGCCCUAUACCUCCAGCCGUGAAUGCCAGACUUUAAGAUUGCCCGGAGGAAGCAAACUCUUCGUAUAAAAAAAGCAGGCCAUCUGCUUAACCCUUGGCUCCACCAUAAGGCACUGGGACUCGGAUUUCUCUAUCUGAUAGAGGUAUUUUCUGUGGCCCUGGGAGCUGUCUGUCUUUCCCCUACCCCCAAGGAUGCCAGGAAGACGUCCACCAUUAGCCAUGUGGCAACCUUUACUUCUAUGCCUCACAAGUGCCUUUCAGAGAGCCCCAAUUCUGCUUUCCCACAAAAUAAACCUAAUGCCAUCAGGCAAAACA